GAGGAGCCACCGCCCAGCCGCUCGCAGGCGCCGCACGGAGUUGCGUCCCGGGGACUUGGGGCCGCAGGGAGGUGAGCGCGGGGCGACGAGCGGGGCAGGACUCACGGCCGCCCAGCCGCAGGCGCCGGAAGGGUCCCGAGGUUGUGCCCGAGCCUGCCCUGGAGCGGUGGUGCGCGGCCAGGAAGGGUGCCCAGUGCCCGGUGCCCGCCCUGCGGAGCGCCUGGGUCCCACGUGGGCUCGGCUGGAGGCCCGGGCUGGCUCAGACGGCGCCGGCGGGGCCGCUGGACCCGGUCUGCUGGCCCCUAGGGCUCGGCUCGGACAGGACGCCUAAGGGGUCCCUGGGCGACGGGGCGCCAGAUGUAGGGGCAAGACGAUUGGGCAGAGAUUUAAACCUCCGGAGGAAGAGAGGAGACUGCGCAGGGCAGUCCCGCCUGCGUCCCAGAAGUGCCUGCAGUUCAGACCCUUCUCUCCCCUCCACUUUCUCCCGGGUGAGCACCGGGCGGACCGGGGCCGAAGUUUGUUGGUUGAGCCAGCCAAGGUGGAAACAGGUUCCCAGACCAGAGGACUGUUGUUAGGUGAUUGGCUGUGAACACCCUGAGGCCAGUGCCCCUCGCUGCUUGGCACUCGGAGAUGCCUGAUUAGCACCUUUAAUCCCUUACCAGUGAGGCAGGUGGAAUUGGCCCCAUUUUACAGAUGGGGAGACUGAGCCACCUGUCUGUCCAGCCACCCUUCCACAGACUGAGGCUUGACACCGGAGCAUCUGUACAGAGCAAGGAGAAGACAAGAACAUGCUCUAAAGCCCUUCACAGCAAGACCCAGGAAGCCGCGGGCAAACUCAGACUCGAAGCCCUCCCGCCUCCUGCCCACAAUGGCCUCUGCUGACAAGAAUGGCGGGAGCGUGUCCUCUGUGUCCAGCAGCCGCCUGCAGAGCCGGAAGCCACCCAACCUCUCCAUCACCAUCCCGCCACCCGAGAAAGAGACCCAGGCCCCUGGCGAGCAGGACAGCAUGCUGCCUGAGGGUUUUCAGAAUAGGAGGCUAAAGAAAAGCCAGCCCAGGACCUGGGCUGCACACACCACCGCCUGCCCUCCCUCCUUCCUCCCCAAGAGGAAGAACCCAGCCUACUUGAAGAGCGUCAGCCUCCAGGAGCCACGCAGCCGAUGGCAGGAGAGUUCAGAGAAGCGCCCUGGCUUCCGCCGCCAGGCCUCACUGUCCCAGAGCAUCCGCAAGGGCGCAGCCCAGUGGUUUGGAGUCAGCGGCGACUGGGAGGGGCAGCGGCAGCAGUGGCAGCGCCGCAGCCUGCACCACUGCAGCAUGCGCUACGGCCGCCUGAAGGCCUCGUGCCAGCGUGACCUGGAGCUCCCCAGCCAGGAGGCACCGUCCUUCCAGGGCACUGAGUCCCCAAAGCCCUGCAAGAUGCCCAAGAUUGUGGAUCCGCUGGCCCGGGGCCGGGCCUUCCGCCACCCGGAGGAGAUGGACAGGCCCCACGCCCCGCACCCACCGCUGACCCCCGGAGUCCUGUCCCUCACCUCCUUCACCAGUGUCCGUUCUGGCUACUCCCACCUGCCACGCCGCAAGAGAAUGUCUGUGGCCCACAUGAGCUUGCAAGCUGCCGCUGCCCUCCUCAAGGGGCGCUCGGUGCUGGAUGCCACCGGACAGCGGUGCCGGGUGGUCAAGCGCAGCUUUGCCUUCCCGAGCUUCCUGGAGGAGGAUGUGGUCGAUGGGGCAGACACGUUUGACUCCUCCUUUUUUAGUAAGGAAGAAAUGAGCUCCAUGCCUGAUGAUGUCUUUGAGUCCCCCCCACUCUCUGCCAGCUACUUCCGAGGGAUCCCACACUCAGCCUCCCCUGUCUCCCCCGAUGGGGUGCAAAUCCCUCUGAAGGAGUAUGGCCGAGCCCCAGUCCCCGGGCCCCGGCGCGGCAAGCGCAUCGCCUCCAAGGUGAAGCACUUUGCCUUUGAUCGGAAGAAGCGGCACUACGGCCUCGGCGUGGUGGGCAACUGGCUGAACCGCAGCUACCGCCGCAGCAUCAGCAGCACUGUGCAGCGGCAGCUGGAGAGCUUCGACAGCCACCGGCCCUACUUCACCUACUGGCUGACCUUCGUCCAUGUCAUCAUCACGCUGCUGGUGAUUUGCACGUAUGGCAUCGCACCCGUGGGCUUUGCCCAGCACGUCACCACCCAGCUGGUGCUGCGGAACAAAGGUGUGUACGAGAGCGUGAAGUACAUCCAGCAGGAGAACUUCUGGGUUGGCCCCAGCUCGAUUGACCUGAUCCACCUGGGGGCCAAGUUCUCACCCUGCAUCCGGAAGGACGGGCAGAUCGAGCAGCUGGUGCUGCGCGAGCGAGACCUGGAGCGGGACUCAGGCUGCUGUGUCCAGAAUGACCACUCCGGAUGCAUCCAGACCCAGCGGAAGGACUGCUCGGAGACUUUGGCCACUUUUGUCAAGUGGCAGGAUGACACUGGGCCCCCCAUGGACAAGUCUGAUCUGGGCCAGAAGCGGACUUCGGGGGCUGUCUGCCACCAGGACCCCAGGACCUGCGAGGAGCCAGCCUCCAGCGGUGCCCACAUCUGGCCCGAUGACAUCACUAAGUGGCCGAUCUGCACAGAGCAGGCCAGGAGCAACCACACAGGCUUCCUGCACAUGGACUGCGAGAUCAAGGGCCGCCCCUGCUGCAUCGGCACCAAGGGCAGCUGUGAGAUCACCACCCGGGAAUACUGUGAGUUCAUGCACGGCUAUUUCCAUGAGGAAGCAACACUCUGCUCCCAGGUGCACUGCUUGGACAAGGUGUGUGGGCUGCUGCCCUUCCUCAACCCUGAGGUCCCAGAUCAGUUCUACAGGCUCUGGCUGUCUCUCUUCCUACAUGCUGGCGUGGUGCACUGCCUCGUGUCUGUGGUCUUUCAAAUGACCAUCCUGAGGGACCUGGAGAAGCUGGCCGGCUGGCACCGUAUCGCCAUCAUCUUCAUCCUCAGUGGCAUCACAGGCAACCUCGCCAGUGCCAUCUUUCUCCCAUACCGGGCAGAGGUGGGCCCGGCCGGCUCACAGUUCGGCCUCCUCGCCUGCCUCUUCGUGGAGCUCUUCCAGAGCUGGCCGCUGCUGGAGAGGCCCUGGAAGGCCUUCCUCAACCUCUCGGCCAUCGUGCUCUUCCUGUUCAUCUGUGGCCUCCUGCCCUGGAUCGACAACAUCGCCCACAUCUUCGGCUUCCUCAGUGGCCUGCUGCUGGCCUUCGCCUUCCUGCCCUACAUCACCUUCGGCACCAGCGACAAGUACCGCAAGCGGGCACUCAUCCUGGUGUCACUGCUGGCCUUUGCCGGCCUCUUCGCCGCCCUCGUGCUGUGGCUGUACAUCUACCCCAUUAACUGGCCCUGGAUCGAGCACCUCACCUGCUUCCCCUUCACCAGCCGCUUCUGCGAGAAGUAUGAGCUGGACCAGGUGCUGCACUGACCGCUGGGCCACACGGCUGCCCCUCAGCCCUGCUGGAACAGGGUCUGCCUGCGAGGGCUGCCCUCUGCAGAGCGCUCUCUGUGUGCCAGAGAGCCAGAGACCCAAGACAGGGCCCGGGCUCUGGACCUGGGUGCCCCCCUGCCAGGCGAGGCUGACUCCGCGUGAGAUGGUUGGUUAAGGCGGGGUUUUUCUGGGGCGUGAGGCCUGUGAGAUCCUGACCCAAGCUCAGGCACACCCAAGGCACCUGCCUCUCUGAGUCUUGGGUCUCAGUUCCUAAUAUCCCGCUCCUUGCUGAGACCAUCUCCUGGGGCAGGGUCCUUUUCUUCCCAGGUCCUCAGCGCUGCCUCUGCUGGUGCCUUCUCCCCCACUACUACUGGAGCGUGCCCUUGCUGGGGACGUGGCUGUGCCCUCAGUUGCCCCCAGGGCUGGGUGCCCACCAUGCCCCUUCCUCUUUCUCCUCCUACCUCUGCCCUGUGAGCCCAUCCAUAAGGCUCUCAGAUGGGACAUUGUGGGAAAGGCUUUGGCCAUGGUCUGGGGGCAGAGAACAAGGGGGGAGACACAAGUAGACCUCAGGUAGAACGACACUGGGCGGAGCCACCCCAGGGCCUGCUCCCAGGGAGUGCUCGAGGCGCAUCAGGCCCGUUUUUUACCAGUUUAUAUCACGGUCUUCAUUUUUAAAAGUAACGCUAACUUUGUACGGACGAUGUCUCAUGGAUUAAAUAAUAUUCUUUAUGGCAGUA